AUUCUGUCUCCAAAAUGCAAGAUUGUUGUAAAAUGGAAUUGUAGGUACAGUUUUCCAACCUUGGAGAUGGCGUUGAUUUACUUGUUUUUACAAUGAGGUUUCUCCAUUGGGCACUUAGGCCAUCAGCUUACUUUAAGCAUUUGCCAAAGGCCCCACCAGCUGGCUGUGAAUUGAUGCAGAUUUUGGUGAGCUGAAAGCUAUAUUCUAGUAAAAGCCACCGAGUCCUGAACAGUCUGAAACCUCCUAAAGAAACCAAGCUCCUCUUACUUUUAUCUUCACAAUGAUAGUUUAUUUUCCAGGAAUUCUAGCCACAGAUACACAUCAUCCCCAGGAUUCUGCUCUGUAUCAUCUCAGCAAGCAGCUAUUACAGAAAUAUCAUAAAGAAGUGAGACCUGUUUACAACUGGACCAAGGCCACCACAGUCUACCUGGACCUGUUCGUCCAUGCUAUAUUGGAUGUGGAUGCAGAGAAUCAAAUAUUAAAGACAAGUGUAUGGUACCAAGAGGUCUGGAAUGAUGAAUUUUUAUCCUGGAACUCCAGCAUGUUUGAUGAGAUUAGAGAGAUCUCCCUACCUCUAAGUGCCAUCUGGGCCCCCGAUAUCAUCAUCAAUGAGUUUGUGGACAUUGAAAGAUACCCUGACCUUCCCUAUGUUUAUGUGAACUCAUCUGGGACCAUUGAGAACUAUAAGCCCAUCCAGGUGGUCUCUGCGUGCAGUUUAGAGACAUAUGCUUUUCCAUUUGAUGUCCAGAAUUGCAGCCUGACCUUCAAGAGCAUUCUGCAUACAGUGGAAGACGUAGACCUGGCCUUUCUGAGGAGCCCAGAAGACAUUCAGCAUGACAAAAAGGCGUUUUUGAAUGACAGUGAGUGGGAACUUCUAUCUGUGUCCUCCACAUACAGCAUCCUGCAGAGCAGCGCUGGAGGAUUUGCACAGAUUCAGUUUAAUGUGGUGAUGCGCAGGCACCCCCUGGUCUAUGUCGUGAGUCUGCUGAUUCCUAGCAUCUUUCUCAUGCUGGUGGACCUGGGGAGCUUCUACCUGCCACCCAACUGCCGAGCCAGGAUUGUGUUCAAGACCAGUGUGCUGGUGGGCUACACCGUCUUCAGGGUCAACAUGUCCAACCAGGUGCCACGGAGUGUAGGGAGCACCCCUCUGAUUGGGCACUUCUUCACCAUCUGCAUGGCCUUCUUGGUUCUCAGCUUAGCUAAGUCCAUCGUGUUGGUCAAAUUCCUCCAUGAUGAGCAGCGUGGUGGACAGGAGCAGCCCUUCUUGUGCCUUCGAGGGGACACCGAUGCUGACAGGCCUAGAGUGGAACCCAGGGCCCAACGUGCUGUGGUAACAGAGUCCUCGCUGUAUGGAGAGCACCUGGCCCAGCCAGGAACCCUGAAGGAAGUCUGGUCGCAGCUUCAAUCUAUCAGCAACUACCUCCAAACUCAGGACCAGACAGACCAACAGGAGGCAGAGUGGCUGGUCCUCCUGUCCCGCUUUGACCGACUGCUCUUCCAAAGCUACCUUUUCAUGCUGGGGAUCUACACCAUCACUCUGUGCUCCCUCUGGGCACUGUGGGGCGGCGUGUGAAGACUGAAGUGUUCUUCAGUAAUUGUGCUGGCACUUAGGAGAGAGAGGAGGGGGAAUAAUAGUGGGUUAAAAAGCUUUCUGGGUCGGGUGUGGUGGUUCUUGCCUAUAGUCCCAGUGCUUUGGGAGGCCAUAGCAGGAGGAUUGCUUGAGCCCAGGAGUUCGAGACCAGCCAGAGCAACAUAGUGAGACCACAUCUCUACCAGUAAAUAAAUAAAUAAAUAAAUAAAUAAAUAAAUAAAUAAAUAGCUGGGCAUAGUGGCUCAUGCCUGUACUCUCAGCUACUUGGGAGGUUGAGGUGGGAGGAUUGCUUGAGCCCAGGAUUUCAAGGCUGCAGUGAGCCAUGAUUGCACCACUGCACCCCAGCCUGGGUGACAGAGCAAGACCCUGUCUCAAAAAAAAUAAAAUAAAAGGCUUUCUGCCUUCAUUGCCUCUCCAUUGAGUCCAGCUUCAUACACCUAAUAGUCUGCUGUGUGACCCAAGGAUCAUAUGUUCAUGAAAAUGUAUAAACAGUAUGAGUAUACAGUAAAAAAGUAAACUUUCCUUCUUAUCCCAGUCCACUCACCCAAAGCAACCACUGUUAGUAAUUUCUUCCAGAAGAUUUCUAGGCACACACAUGCAUCUAUGUAUGGUUAAGCAGUUUUUUAAAAAGUGUAAGAUAGCUCCAUCUUCCAGCCCUGCCUUGGCCAUUUAUUCAGUCACCCAUUCAACAAAACCUUUAUUGAGUAUUAAGUCCUAGGCAUUAUGUUAGGCACACCAGAGAAUACAAAAUAAGUCAGCACAGGUUAUUAUUCACUUGUUGUGAUUCCCAUGGUCAACCUGGUACCAACCAACCAGAGCAUAAAAUUCCUGCCAUAUCCCUCACCUUCUGAGGCUCUUGUUACCACUUCCCAGCUAAGUCCACUGCCUCCACCCUCUUCCUGUGCCCCUUCAGCAGUGCAUCCCCACUGGAGAGAACCCAGGUGCCAAGGCUUCUUUUUUUUUUUUUGAGGCAGAGUCUUGCUCUGUCACCAGAUUGGAGUGCAGUGGUGCAAUCUUGGCUCACUGUAACCUCCACCUCCCGGGUUCAAGCAAUUCCCCUGCCUCAGCCUCCCGAGUAGCUGGAACUACAGGUGCAUGCCACCACACCCAGCUAAUUUUCUGUAUUUUAGUAGCAGGUGCCAAGGCUUCUAAGCCCAGUCUAGCACAUCAUUUAGUCCACACACAAGGGGCAAUGCAUGGAGUGGGAGGACAGGCAUAGUUCACGGUCCUUUGCUUCAAGGAAGUUAUAAUCCACUGUCCCUGAACUAGUCAGCUAGGAAAUACUACACACUAAGUUGCUUUAAGAGAGAUUUAUUUUCUCACCAGUCUGGAAGCUAGAAGCCUAAGAUCAAGGUGCAAACAGGGUGGGUGGCUUUCUUCUGAGCCCUGUCCUUGGCUUGCAGGUUGCUGACUUCUUGCUUUGUUUUCACAUGACCUUUCCUCUGUGCAUGCUCAUGUCUGUGUCCAGAUUUUCUCUUCUAACAAGGGCACCAGUGUUGUUGGUUUAGGGUCCAUCCUAGUGACCUCUUUUAACCUUAAUCACUUUUUUCAAGGCCCUAUGUUCAAACAGUCAUAUUCUGAGUACUAGGGGUUAGGAUGUCAACAUAUGAAUUUUGGGGAGUGGGCAGCAGACAAAGGGGACAUAUUUCAGCCCAUAACACUAGUGAUUCCGGAGGUUUAGCAAGUCCAGAUUCUGCAGAGUAGGCUGGCAGGCUGGAGACCUGCUGACAGUCUUAACGCUGUCAGUAGAAGACACAAAAGUCCAAAAGCUGUUUGCUAGAAACUUUUUCCAGCACUAAAAUUGCCUUUAGAAAAAUCUGCCCCCCUCCAUCCCCCCAAAGAAAAAGAAUUUAAAUUCAAACAGCCUUUACCUGCAUCUUCCCUCUCUCAUUACCUCCCAGUUAGUGCUCAGCGCCAAUUGUCCAUGAAAUUCCACUGCUGCUGUUAAUGAAAUGAGGAACAUAAGAAGUUUGUGAACAGGAAGUGUCCAUGCAAACCUCCACCUGUUUCCUUCCUCACUUCCUACUUUCUACUGCUGGCCUCCUCUGCUUUGACGUGCUCAGUUAGGCAUCACGGUCCUGAUGUCACCUUAGCUUGCCAUCCAUGUCGAUUCUGGCUUUCUCCACUUCCUCCUCCAGUUAACAGAGGAGGAAAGGAGGAAAAGGCCUGAGGUGAACUCCUCACUGUGGGGUCUCUCUCCUUCCCAACUAUGUCUUAGAGAAAGCACCAGUGUCAGAGUCAGGAGUCCUGAUGAUUACGGUCCUGGCUCUGCCAUUACCUAGCCAGGGGACCUCUGUGAGCUUAACUUCUCAGACUUCAACUUACCUUAUUUGAAAUUGGGGCUGUUUAUAUUUGCUCUACCCCUAUCAAAGAGUUAUGAGGAUCAAAAUGAAAAAAUGUAUUGAACAAUGCUUUGAAAAGUAAAUAAUGGGGCGUGGUGGCUCACGCCUAUAAUCCCAACACUUUGGGAGGCUGAGGUGGGUGGAUUACCUGAGGUCAGGAGUUUGAGACCAGCCUGACCAACAUGGAGAAACCCUGUCUCUACUAAAAAUACAAAAUUAGCCAGGCGUGGUGGCACAUGCCUGUAAUCCCACCUACUCGGGGGGCUGAGGCAGGAGAAUCGCUUGAACCCAGGAGGUGGAGGUUGCGGUGAGCCGAGAUCGUGCCAUUGCACUCCAGCCCGGGCAACAAGAGCUAAACUCUAUCUCAAAAAAAAAAAAAAGUUUAAAGUGCUUUGGGAAGGGGGAGGGAUAGCAUUAGAAGAUAUACCUAAUGUUAAUGGGUGCAGCACAGCAACGUGGCACGUGUAUACAUAUGUAACAAACCUGCACGUUGUGCACAUGUACCCUAAAACUUAAAGUAUAAUUUAAAAAAAAGUAAAUAAUGCAUCACAAAAUAAAGAUAAGACCUGCUUGCUAUCAACA